AUGCACUUGAGCAGGGAAGAAAUCCACAAGGACUCACCAGUCUCCUGGUCUGCAGAGAAGACAGAAUCAACAUGAGCACAGCAGGAAAAGUAAUCAAAUGCAAAGCAGCUGUGCUAUGGGAGUUAAAGAAACCCUUUUCCAUUGAGGAGGUGGAGGUUGCACCUCCUAAGGCCCAUGAAGUUCGUAUUAAGAUGGUGGCUGUAGGAAUCUGUGGCACAGAUGACCACGUGGUUAGUGGUACCAUGGUGACCCCACUUCCUGUGAUUUUAGGCCAUGAGGCAGCCGGCAUCGUGGAGAGUGUUGGAGAAGGGGUGACUACAGUCAAACCAGGUGAUAAAGUCAUCCCACUCGCUAUUCCUCAGUGUGGAAAAUGCAGAAUUUGUAAAAACCCGGAGAGCAACUACUGCUUGAAAAACGAUGUAAGCAAUCCUCAGGGGACCCUGCAGGAUGGCACCAGCAGGUUCACCUGCAGGAGGAAGCCCAUCCACCACUUCCUUGGCAUCAGCACCUUCUCACAGUACACAGUGGUGGAUGAAAAUGCAGUAGCCAAAAUUGAUGCAGCCUCGCCUCUAGAGAAAGUCUGUCUCAUUGGCUGUGGAUUUUCAACUGGUUAUGGGUCUGCAGUCAAUGUUGCCAAGGUCACCCCAGGCUCUACCUGUGCUGUGUUUGGCCUGGGAGGGGUCGGCCUAUCUGCUAUUAUGGGCUGUAAAGCAGCUGGGGCAGCCAGAAUCAUUGCGGUGGACAUCAACAAGGACAAAUUUGCAAAGGCCAAAGAGUUGGGUGCCACUGAAUGCAUCAACCCUCAAGACUACAAGAAACCCAUCCAGGAGGUGCUAAAGGAAAUGACUGAUGGAGGUGUGGAUUUUUCAUUUGAAGUCAUCGGUCGGCUUGACACCAUGAUGGCUUCCCUGUUAUGUUGUCAUGAGGCAUGUGGCACAAGUGUCAUCGUAGGGGUACCUCCUGAUUCCCAAAACCUCUCAAUGAACCCUAUGCUGCUACUGACUGGACGUACCUGGAAGGGAGCUAUUCUUGGUGGCUUUAAAAGUAAAGAAUGUGUCCCAAAACUUGUGGCUGAUUUUAUGGCUAAGAAGUUUUCAUUGGAUGCAUUAAUAACCCAUGUUUUACCUUUUGAAAAAAUAAAUGAAGGAUUUGACCUGCUUCACUCUGGGAAAAGUAUCCGUACCAUUCUGAUGUUUUGAGACAAUACAGAUGUUUUCCCUUGUGGCAGUCUUCAGCCUCCUCUACCCUACAUGAUCUGGAGCAACAGCUGGGAAAUAUCAUUAAUUCUGCUCAUCACAGAUUUUAUCAAUAAAUUACAUUUGGGGGCUUUCCAAAGAAAUGGAAAUUGAUGUAAAAUUAUUUUUCAAGCAAAUGUUUAAAAUCCAAAUGAGAACUAAAUAAAGUGUUGAACAUCAGCUGGGGAAUUGAAGCCAAUAAACCUUCCUUCUUAACCA